AUUCAGAAGGCAUCAUUUUGGGGAAGGCAGCAGCCGGUUUUUCAGAGCCAGCGAGUGGCCCUGCCAGCUGCUGAGCAGGGCAAGCUGAGAAGGGUGGUGGUGUGCAAGUGUUAUUCUCUCUUUUUGUUUUUGUUUUUGUUUUUUGAGAUGGAGUCUUACUCUGUCGUCCAGGCUGGAGUGAGUGCCGUGGCAUGAUCUCGGCUCACUGCAACCUCCGCCUCCUGGGUUCAAGCGAUUCUCCUGCCUCAGCCUCCCGAGUAACUGGGACUACAGGCACCUGCCACCAUGCUCGGCUAGUUUUUGGUAUUUUUAUUUAUUAUUUAUUUAUUUAUUUUGAGACCGAGUCUCGCUCUGUCGCCCAGGCUCUAGUGCAGUGGCCCAAUCUCGGCUCACUGCAAGCUCCGCCUCCCGCGUUCACGCCAUUCUCCUGCCUCAGCCUCGCGAGCAGCUGGGACUACAGGUGCCCGCCACCACGCCCGGCUAAUUUUUUGUAUUUUUAGUAGAGACGGGGUUUCACCGUGUUAGCCAGGAUGGUCUCGAUUUCCUGACCUCGUGAUCCGCGCGCCUCUGCCUCCAAAGUGCUGGGAUUACAGGCCCGAGCCGCCGCACCCGGCCUGCAGGUGUUGUUCUGACCCCAGCUCCACUGUGCCAGCCCGACUUGAGAUGCCAAGUAUCUUGGGCCUGAGGAUUGAGGCCUAGAGAGAGGCAGGCGUUCCUCAGAGUCACAGGGAAUGGCGGCGCCUGGACUGGGACUCAGCCCAGCUGCUUGGCCUGACCCUCUCACAGCAUAAUUUCCCGGCACCUGGAGGCCGCGCUUAGAAGCCGCCCAGUGCCCUGAGCGUCUCCAUGGCCUGCCUGAGCCCCUCGCAGCUCCAGAAGUUCCAACAGGAUGGAUUCCUGGUGCUGGAAGGAUUCUUGUCUGCGGAAGAGUGUGUGGCCAUGCAACAAAGGAUUGGCGAGAUAGUGGCUGAAAUGGAUGUUCCUCUCCACUGCCGCACAGAAUUCUCCACCCAGGAAGAGGAGCAGCUUCGAGCCCAGGGCAGCACAGACUAUUUCUUGAGCAGUGGUGACAAGAUUCGAUUCUUCUUUGAGAAAGGCGUUUUUGAUGAGAAAGGAAAUUUCCUGGUCCCUCCGGAGAAAUCCAUCAACAAAAUUGGCCACGCUCUGCACGCCCACGACCCCGUCUUCAAGAGCAUCACACACUCCUUCAAGGUGCAGACCUUGGCCAGAAGUCUGGGCCUCCAGAUGCCCGUGGUGGUGCAGAGCAUGUACAUCUUUAAGCAACCUCACUUUGGCGGUGAAGUCUCCCCUCAUCAGGACGCCUCCUUCCUGUACACGGAGCCCCUGGGCCGGGUGCUGGGCGUGUGGAUCGCAGUGGAGGAUGCCACGCUGGAGAACGGCUGUCUCUGGUUCAUCCCUGGCUCCCACACCAGUGGUGUGUCAAGAAGGAUGGUCCGGGCCCCUGUUGGCUCAGCGCCUGGUACCAGCUUCCUUGGGUCAGAGCCAGCCCGGGAUAACAGCCUCUUUGUGCCCACCCCAGUGCAGAGAGGGGCCCUGGUCCUCAUCCAUGGAGAAGUGGUACACAAGAGCAAGCAGAACCUCUCUGACCGCUCGCGCCAGGCCUACACUUUCCACCUCAUGGAGGCCUCUGGCACCACCUGGAGCCCGGAGAACUGGCUCCAGCCAACAGCUGAACUGCCCUUUCCCCAACUGUACACCUAAAGGCUCUCGCAGGGCAGGAGCCCUCGCCCCUCCCGGGUGAAGCUGUGGGCUGUAAACACCAGUGCCUUGCUCAGCCUCCUGGUUGCAACAGGGAGGUCUUGUCUCCCCUCCUGGGCUUUCCUCCUGCCCUGUGGGCAGCAGCCUAGGCUGGGUCAGGGGCUUCCCUAAGAUCUUCACCUCUCUGCCUCCCUACUGCCCCAACAUAGCCUUGAGGAGGCUUCUCAGCCACCAAAGGGUUCUGGCCCCUUCUCACUCUCCUCUCCUCUCAGAUGGAACUCUGGUUAUUAUGGUGUUAGUUAUCGAAUAAAAACGACUUCAGAAUGCA